AGAGGAGUCCCGCGUUCGGGGAGUAUGUCAAGGCCGUGACCCGUGUAUUAUUGUCCGAGUGGCCGGAACGGGAGCCAACAUGGCAGCGGGGUUCGGGCGAUGCUGCAGGGUCCUGAGAAGUAUUUCUCGUUUUCAUUGGAGAUCACAGCAUACAAAAGCCAAUCGACAACGUGAACCAGGAUUAGGAUUUAGUUUUGAGUUCACCGAACAGCAGAAAGAAUUUCAAGCUACUGCUCGUAAAUUUGCCAGAGAGGAAAUCAUCCCAGUGGCUGCAGAAUAUGAUAAAACUGGUGAAUAUCCAGUCCCCCUAAUUAGAAGAGCCUGGGAACUUGGUUUAAUGAACACACACAUUCCAGAGAACUGUGACUACAGUGUUUGCCCACUUUUGGAAGCUUGCACUCUAUACCUAGAUGCGUUUUUCCUUCUUCUAACUGGUUCCAACCUUAACUUGCACCUAAACCUUGGAGGUCUUGGACUUGGAACUUUUGAUGCUUGUUUAAUUAGUGAAGAAUUGGCUUAUGGAUGUACAGGGGUUCAGACUGCUAUUGAAGGAAAUUCUUUGGGGCAAAUGCCUAUUAUUAUUGCUGGAAAUGAUCAACAAAAGAAGAAGUAUUUGGGGAGAAUGACUGAGGAGCCAUUGAUGUGUGCUUAUUGUGUAACAGAACCUGGAGCAGGCUCUGAUGUAGCUGGUAUAAAGACCAAAGCAGAAAAGAAAGGAGAUGAGUAUAUUAUUAAUGGUCAGAAGAUGUGGAUAACCAACGGAGGAAAAGCUAAUUGGUAUUUUUUAUUGGCACGUUCUGAUCCAGAUCCUAAAGCUCCUGCUAAUAAAGCCUUUACUGGAUUCAUUGUGGAAGCAGAUACCCCAGGAAUUCAGAUUGGGAGAAAGGAAUUAAACAUGGGCCAGCGAUGUUCAGAUACUAGAGGAAUUGUCUUCGAAGAUGUGAAAGUGCCUAAAGAAAAUGUUUUAAUUGGUGACGGAGCUGGUUUCAAAGUUGCAAUGGGAGCUUUUGAUAAAACCAGACCUGUAGUAGCUGCUGGUGCUGUUGGAUUAGCACAAAGAGCUUUGGAUGAAGCUACCAAGUAUGCCCUGGAAAGGAAAACUUUCGGAAAGCUACUUGUAGAGCACCAAGCAAUAUCAUUUAUGCUGGCUGAAAUGGCAAUGAAAGUUGAACUAGCUAGAAUGAGUUACCAGAGAGCAGCUUGGGAGGUUGAUUCUGGUCGUCGAAAUACCUAUUAUGCUUCUAUUGCAAAGGCAUUUGCUGGAGAUAUUGCAAAUCAGUUAGCUACUGAUGCUGUGCAGAUACUUGGAGGCAAUGGAUUUAAUACAGAAUAUCCUGUAGAAAAACUAAUGAGGGAUGCCAAAAUCUAUCAGAUUUAUGAAGGUACUUCACAAAUUCAAAGACUUAUUGUAGCCCGUGAACACAUUGACAAGUACAAAAAUUAAAAAAAUUACUGUAGAAAUAUUGAAUAACUAGAACACAAGCCACUGUUUCAGCUCCAGAAAAAAGAAAGGGCUUUAACGUUUUUUCCAGUGAAAACAAAUCCUCUUAUAUUAAAUCUAAGCAACUGCUUAUUAUAGUAGUUUAUACUUUUGCUUAACUCUGUUAUGUCUCUUAAGCAGGUUUGGUUUUUAUUAAAAUGAUGUGUUUUCUUUAGUACCACUUUACUUGAAUUACAUUAACCUAGAAAACUACAUAGGUUAUUUUGAUCUCUUAAGAUUAAUGUAGCAGAAAUUUCUUGGAAUUUUAUUUUUGUAAUGACAGAAAAGUGGGCUUAGAAAGUAUUCAAGAUGUUACAAAAUUUACAUUUAGAAAAUAUUGUAGUAUUUGAAUACUGUCAACUUGACAGUAACUUUGUAGACUUAAUGGUAUUAUUAAAGUUCUUUUUAUUGCAGUUUGGAAAGCAUUUGUGAAACUUUCUGUUUGGCACAGAAACAGUCAAAAUUUUGACAUUCAUAUUCUCCUAUUUUACAGCUACAAGAACUUUCUUGAAAAUCUUAUUUAAUUCUGAGCCCAUAUUUCACUUACCUUAUUUAAAAUAAAUCAAUAAAGCUUGCCUUAAAUUAUUUUUAUAUGACUGUUGGUCUCUAGGUAGCCUUUGGUCUAUUGUACACAAUCUCAUUUCAUAUGUUUGCAUUUUGGCAAAGAACUUAAUAAAAUUGUUCAGUGCUUAUUAUCAUAUCUUUCUGUAUUUUUUCCAGGAAAUUUCAUUACUUCGUGUAAUAGUGUAUAUUUCUUGUAUUUACUAUGAUGAAAAAAGGUCGUUUUAAUUUUGAAUUGAAUAAAGUUACCUGUUCAUUUUUUAUUAGAUAUUUUAAAGACUUCAGAAAAUAUAAAUAUGAAAUAAUUUAAGAACCCAAA